AGAGAGCUGUUUACUAGGCACGACUGCGAAGGCAAGGGGGCACCAGCUCAGGACUGCAUCUGCCUGCCAUUUCCCUUCCACUCCUCCUUUCUGGAGUCUGACAUUAGAAAGCCAGCGAGAAGGAAGAUUCAAACAACCAACCCUGAUUUCCUGCUUCUCCUUUUCAUGAGUGUUCCUGUGGUCUCUGCACCUCCUUUCUGUCCCCCGGCAGAGGGCAGUAGAGAUGGCCGGCCCAAGGCCUCGGUGGCGCGACCAGCUGCUGUUCAUGAGCAUCAUAGUCCUCGUGAUUGUGGUCAUCUGCCUGAUGUUUUACGCUCUUCUCUGGGAGGCUGGCAACCUCACUGACCUGCCCAACCUGAGAAUCGGCUUCUAUAACUUCUGCCUGUGGAAUGAGGACACCAGCACCCUACAGUGUCACCAGUUCCCUGAGCUGGAAGCCCUGGGGGUGCCUCGGGUUGGCCUGGGCCUGGCCAGGCUUGGCGUGUACGGGUCCCUGGUCCUCACCCUCUUUGCCCCCCAGCCUCUCCUCCUAGCCCAGUGCAACAGUGAUGAGAGAGCGUGGCGGCUGGCAGUGGGCUUCCUGGCUGUGUCCUCUGUGCUGCUGGCAGGCGGCCUGGGCCUCUUCCUCUCCUAUGUGUGGAAGUGGGUCAGGCUCUCCCUCCCGGGGCCUGGGUUUCUAGCUCUGGGCAGCGCCCAGGCCUUACUCAUCCUCUUGCUUAUAGCCAUGGCUGUGUUCCCUCUGAGGGCUGAGAGGGCUGAGAGCAAGCUUGAGAGCUGCUAAAGGCUUACGUGAUUGCAAGGGUUCAGUUCCAACCAUGGUCAGAGGUGGCACAUCUGCUCAGCCAUCUCAUUUUACAGCUAACGCUGAUCUCCAGCUCCAGCGAUGGAACCCACUACAGAGGAGGUGGGGCCCCUGUGUCAAAGAGGCCGAGGGGCAGCAAGGGCAGCCAGGGCACCUGUGACUUCUUAGUACAAGAUUGUCUGUCCUUCAGGACUUCCAAGGCUCCCAAAGACUCCCUAAACCAUGCAGCUCAUUGUCACACCAAUUCCUGCUUUAAUUAAUGGAUCUGAGCAAAUCUUCCUCUAGCUUCAGGAGGGUGGGGAGGGAGUGAUUGCUGUCAUGGGGCCAGACUUCCAGGCUGAUUUGCCAAAUGCCAAAAUGAAACCUAGCAAAGAACUUACGGCAACAAACGAGGACAUUAAAAGAGCGAGCACCUCAGUGUCUCUGGGGACAUGGUUAAGGAGCUUCCACUCAGCCCACCAUAGUGAGUGGGCCGCCAUAAGCCAUCACUGGAACUCCAACCCCAGAGGUCCAGGAGUGAUCUCUGAGUGACUCAACAAAGACAGGACACAUGGGGUACAAAGACAAGGCUUGACUGCUUCAAAGCUUCCCUGGACCUGAAGCCAGACAGGGCAGAGGCGUCCGCUGACAAAUCACUCCCAUGAUGAGACCCUGGAGGACUCCAAAUCCUCGCUGUGAACAGGACUGGACGGCUGCACACAAACAAACGCUGCCACCCUCCACUUCCCAACCCAGAACUUGGAAAGACAUUAGCACAACUUACGCAUUGGGGAAUUGUGUGUAUUUUCUAGCACUUGUGUAUUGGAAAACCUGUAUGGCAGUGAUUUAUUCAUAUAUUCCUGUCCAAAGCCACACUGAAAACAGAGGCAGAGACAUGUACUCUGGUGUGAUCUCUUGUCCUCAGUGUCUCUUCUGGGCUCCUGUCCCUCUUGCUUUAUAGCUAGCUGCCCGGGGACCAAGGUACAGGUGAAAGCAAGGUAGCAGCUUGCGGGAGGAGGCCUGUCUGGCUUACCAGUCUAUACACUGUGGCCUCAACCUCCCAGACAGGGCAGAGAACUGUGGGCAGCUCGUUUGCUUUCUAGGCUGGCUGGAGAGGUGGGAGCUCAUUGAUAGACUCAUGAUGGAAACUAUUUUUGAAACAGGCUUCCUCCUUCAGGAGAGAUCAUGCGGACUAAACUGUAGCAAUUCCAGUGCA